GAGAACUCUUGAGACCGGGAGCCCAGCUGCCCACCCUCUGGACAUUCACCCAGCCAGGUGGUCUCGUCACCUCAGAGGCUCCGCCAGACUCCUGCCCAGGCCAGGACUGAGGCAAGCCUCAAGGCACUUCUAGGACCUGCCUCUUCUCACCAAGAUGAACUCACUGGUUUCUUGGCAGCUACUGCUUUUCCUCUGUGCCACCCACUUUGGGGAGCCAUUAGAAAAGGUGGCCUCUGUGGGGAAUUCUAGACCCACAGGCCAGCAGCUAGAAUCCCUGGGCCUCCUGGCCCCCGGGGAGCAGAGCCUGCCGUGCACCGAGAGGAAGCCAGCUGCUACUGCCAGGCUGAGCCGUCGGGGGACCUCGCUGUCCCCGCCCCCCGAGAGCUCCGGGAGCCCCCAGCAGCCGGGCCUGUCCGCCCCCCACAGCCGCCAGAUCCCCGCACCCCAGGGCGCGGUGCUGGUGCAGCGGGAGAAGGACCUGCCGAACUACAACUGGAACUCCUUCGGCCUGCGCUUCGGCAAGCGGGAGGCGGCACCAGGGAACCACGGCAGAAGCGCUGGGCGGGGCUGAGGGCGCAGGUGCGGGGCAGUGAACUUCAGACCCCAAAGGAGUCAGAGCAUGCGGGGCGGGGGCGGGGGGCGGGGACGUAGGGCUAAGGGAGGGGGCGCUGGAGCUUCCAACCCGAGGCAAUAAAAGAAAUGUUGCGUAACUCA